GCCCGCGCCCGCACCUCCCCGGCUUGCUCGGGCUGGGAUUCCCGGGCGCCCCGCCCUGGACCUCGGGCUCCCCGCCUCGUGACGCCGUCCUCCCCCUCCGCUCCGGCCCGUAGUGGCGGGGAGGGGUCCGCAGGGCGGGGGAGCGGGGAGCCCAGCGCCGGGAUGCCUGCUCCCGCGUCCUGCCCUGGGCCAUCGGGAUGAAUUGGGCAGUCCCCAGGGCCCCUUUUAACAGCCCUGGUUCAAAGCCCAGUGUGGACUCGGGUGCGGGGACAGACGGCGUUUGGAGAGCUUUUUCCAGAAACUGUCCGGAGCCCAGCUCGGGUUCUGACAUCGCCCCUAAGGAUUUCUCAGGGAAGGCAUCCCAGCCACGGCUUUUCCUGCCGACUUUGCUCUUCCUACCGCCGCGCGGGGCGACCCACGUACCGCGUGCUCAGAGGGCGGCUACACGCCCCAUCCCCCAGCCUCGGUGCCGCCUGCCAGCCCGCGGAGGGAAGCGGUCCCCGACCCGGCCCCGGCCCCCACGUUCUGGGGCGCGAGUCCUGAGAAGGCGCCUAACGUGUAGCGCGCCUGGACCCUCUCGAGAUGCUGCCCUUAGAGUGGGAUGAAAGUCUGGGGAGGAACGCCUUGUCACCGGCAAAAACAGCCUUUCUCUUGGUCUUCGUCUGCAUCCUCCUUUUCAAAAUAUCUUGAUUUCCCCCGCGCACCCCUGACCCGGCUGCAGCACCGGCCCUCCGAGCGGGAAGAGCCCCGUGAAGGCUCCGCAGAGCGAUCUACCCCGCGCUCUUGUCCGUGCCCAGAAAGCGGGUUCCACUUGGCAGGGAUUAUUUUAAACUGCUACCAGCAAUUCAUUCACCUGACACCCGACACCGGCAGCCCAGCCCGCCGGAGGCGAGACAGGAUUGUCCGGUGCCCGCUAGAGGUCGCCAAACGGAGUCCUUUUGCGCUGGUUCUUAAGUGGAUUCCUAGUGAAAAGGCAGACAACUGAAAAUAUUAUGUCUACUUUGAGAAUUCCUCCAGCAACCCAUACCUAAUAAGAAGGAUAGAAGAACUCAACAAGACUGCAAGUGGCAACGUGGAAGCAAAAGUAGUAUGCUUUUAUAGACGACGUGAUAUUUCCAACACACUUAUAAUGCUCGCAGAUAAGCAUGCUAAAGAAAUUGAGGAAGAAUCUGAAACAACAGUUGAGGCUGACUUGACCGAUAAGCAGAAACAUCAGUUGAAACAUAGGGAACUCUUUUUGUCACGCCAGUAUGAAUCUCUGCCCGCAACACAUAUCAGGGGAAAGUGCAGUGUUGCCCUUCUGAAUGAGACAGAAUCAGUAUUGUCAUAUCUUGAUAAGGAGGAUACCUUCUUCUACUCAUUGGUCUAUGACCCCUCAUUGAAAACACUAUUAGCUGACAAAGGUGAAAUCAGAGUGGGACCUAGAUAUCAAGCAGACAUUCCAGAAAUGCUGUUAGAAGGAGAAUCAGAUGAGAGGGAACAAUCAAAAUUGGAAGUUAAAGUUUGGGAUCCAAAUAGCCCACUUACGGAUCGACAGAUUGACCAGUUUUUAGUUGUAGCACGUGCUGUUGGGACAUUCGCCAGAGCCCUGGAUUGCAGCAGUUCUGUGAGGCAGCCUAGUUUGCAUAUGAGUGCUGCUGCAGCUUCCCGAGACAUCACCUUGUUUCACGCUAUGGAUACAUUGUAUAGACACAGCUAUGAUUUGAGCAGUGCCAUUAGUGUCUUAGUACCACUCGGAGGACCUGUUUUAUGCAGAGAUGAAAUGGAGGAAUGGUCAGCCUCUGAAGCUAGCUUAUUUGAAGAGGCACUGGAAAAAUAUGGCAAAGACUUCAAUGACAUACGGCAAGAUUUUCUUCCUUGGAAAUCAUUGACUAGCAUCAUUGAAUAUUAUUACAUGUGGAAAACUACUGACAGAUAUGUGCAACAGAAACGUCUAAAAGCAGCAGAAGCUGAGAGUAAACUGAAACAAGUAUAUAUCCCAACCUACAAACCAAAUCCCAACCAAAUAUCCACUAGUAAUGGGAAGCCUGGUGCUGUGAAUGGAGCUGUGGGGACCACGUUCCAGCCUCAGAAUCCUCUCUUAGGGAGAGCCUGUGAGAGCUGCUAUGCUACACAGUCUCACCAGUGGUAUUCUUGGGGCCCACCUAAUAUGCAGUGUAGAUUAUGUGCAAUUUGUUGGCUUUAUUGGAAAAAAUAUGGAGGCUUGAAAAUGCCCACCCAGUCAGAAGAAGAGAAGUUAUCUCCUAGCCCAACUACAGAGGACCCUCGUGUUAGAAGUCACGUGUCCCGCCAGGCCAUGCAGGGAAUGCCAGUCCGAAACACUGGGAGUCCAAAGUCUGCAGUGAAGACCCGCCAAGCUUUCUUCCUUCAUACUACAUAUUUCACAAAAUUUGCUCGUCAGGUCUGCAAAAAUACCCUCCGGCUGCGGCAGGCAGCAAGACGGCCGUUUGUUGCUAUUAAUUAUGCUGCCAUUAGGGCAGAAUAUGCAGACAGACAUGCUGAACUAUCUGGAAGUCCACUGAAAAGCAAAAGCACUAGGAAGCCUUUGGCAUGUAUCAUUGGGUAUUUAGAGAUCCAUCCUGCAAAGAAACCUAAUGUAAUUCGAUCUACACCAAGCCUGCAAACCCCAACUACCAAGCGGAUGCUAACAACUCCAAAUCACACAUCUCUGAGCAUUCUGGGGAAAAGAAACUACAGUCAUCACAAUGGUCUGGAUGAACUCACGUGCUGUGUGUCAGACUGAGCUUUCCCUGAUUCAUUCUACAAUCCAAGACUUGCUGCACUGUCCUGCUGAUGUUCACAGCCGUGCCUGGGAAGAAGGCAGCCCCACUCCCAGUACAUUUCAGUGGGAGACCUCUGCGUGCAUCCAUGGAGACGCAAUGGGGCGGGGAAGGAACUGUGGGAGUGCACGUUCCAAAUCCUGUGUCUCCACGUGUGGAUCAGCAGCACCUCGCUUUCUUGUCAGAGACCUCGCUGUUACGGAGCGAGACCUGCUGAGAAUUGAGGGGCUGAGGGAACCCCUCCACCUCCUCCCUUCUGCAGCGCCCUGCGCCCCACCCAGCAACAGCGGCCACUUGGCAGUGGGGCUGCUGCAAGCUCAGAGCCGCUGCCACCCUGCAUGUGUCCGCUCAGCUCGGUCUUAUGCUGUAUAGUUACUAAAUAUGUACAGGAGGGCCAUGGCAUCUUUCUGAAUGGAUUUUUCUUAAGAAAUGCGCCAGUGUUUAUGAGGUUCAAGGUAUUUCCCUGUCCUUGCUGUUACCGUCACUCAGCUUUUUCUCGAUAGGCUUCAUCCUUGUUUUUUUGAAAUGGGGGAAUUUGCUGUUUACCCUCUGCAUUCCUAUAUGUGACCCUCCCUCCUACUCCUCCAAGGAACAGAAUUACCGAGGUUCUGACAAAAGAUAAGCCUGUAAACUCAUCAUCUGUGUUUUGUGGUUGGAGAGAAACUGGUGUUCUGCCCGGCUCUGCUUGGUCACAGACAGCUCCAGCAAGAGCAGUUGUUAAAAGUGCCAAGCGUGUGUAUCACUGUGACAAGCCGUUUGCUUACUGCCCUGUUCCCUUGCAGCCAAACCAGCUGAUGAAGAACUGCUGCCAGGUGGGUCCUACAGCAGGUCACAAAUGACCUAGUUUCAUUUUAAGCAGACAGACUCUGUUUGGCCUAGAGGUGUGGAGUGAGAGAACUGUGUUUGUGGGUAUGAGUCUGUGUGGCCAACCCCAUGACCCCCACCCCUCCAGCCCAACAUCUUGUGAGCACAUGUGACCUAGGCCCCGGGGGACCUGCCUGCUCCUUUGGCUUGGGCUCUUCGUGUUUCCCACCUGCCCUCGGCACGAGCCCUUGGUGGCAUCACAGUUGGCCACUCAGCUGUGCUGAGUAGCUGUGCUACUUGUGCUGGCAGCUGCAAGGAUAGGAAUAGCUCAGCGCCCGAUGAGCUCCCUGAGCAGAUGUGAGGCUGGCAACUCCCCUGCCCUCUGUUUGCAGGCACAGGGUCACAGUCCCAAGAAAGACAACUGGAGUCUGAUCUCCCAGCCAUCUCUGGGGUUACUAGGAGGCAGCUGGAUGGCAGAUACGAGAGGCCCAAAUAGCCAAGCUGUUGCAAGACAGAGUGGCUACAAUUGAAUUGACACCCUGGGAAGCACGAGGUAACUUGGUAAGGAUAAUGAUGCUGUAGAUGUCUGUGUCCUCGGAGGCUGAGCUCCGCUUGGCAGAGAGAGCGUGCUGUGUGAGGUGGAGGGCGGUUUUGCAGACAUCUCAGCUUCUUUUCUGAGGAGGAGUUGGUUCUCAUCUUAGGCUUCUGCAAGGGCGAGCAUGGGAUGUCUCCACCACCACCCACUCUUGGAGCUGUGCUGGGUCUUGGCUUGGGGCGCUGAGGGUGGGGCCUGUGUCAGAAGCAUUUGGUGAGAGGGGUGGAGGUGGCAGGCAGGGGUUCUCCUCAGGGUUCCCACUGAGGGGUCCCUUCAGCAAAGACCUGGGAGGAGGUGCCGCAUCACGUGGAUGUUUCUUCCCUAAAGAAAAAGACACAGGAAAGCUGUCUGUCUGUACCCUGCUCUGGAUUUAUUGUCGUACUUGGACCCAGAAGGGGAAAUGAUUCCCUCACCCUUUCACUUUCUCUCUGAACCCCUACUAAGUGGUGACUGCAGAUUCUGGAAACAAUUAGCUGCCCGUGACUCAGCUGCCAGCUUCAUUUUCUCUGCCUUUUGGGAGAGGCCCUCUCACCCAGGCCCAAGAGAUUUGGAGACAGGAGUCAGGCCAGGUCUGAAGCAGGAGAAGGGAGGCCCCUCCUAUCUACCCAGUUGACAUUUGGCUUUGGGAAAAGCGCAGCUUGUUCGAGCCACGUGUGCCAAGCAGGCUUUUCCUUCCUCUUGUAAGUAAAGCUCGUGGUUCUGUAGUCCAGUCAUCCUAGGAGGGUGAUGUUGACUGAGACUUCACGCUCUCCCUUUGUCUCUGGAAACUGCCCCCUCGUUCUGACAGAAUCCCCCAGGCAAUGGAGGAAGGGUGCCGAGGCGCCUCUAGUCUGUGCCUUUGCCGUUGGAAGCAUUUGGUGCUGAGAGGGUUUCCCAGCCACCCGCUCCCUUUCUGGGGCCAUGGUGUCCCUGCUGUGUGUCAGUGGCAUGUCACUGUGGUUCAGUGAGCACAUGGGUGGACGUGCAGAGACUGUCUGCGCAGCCCCCAGCAGACAUGCCCCUGGGGUGAGGACACAGGCUCUGCAGGCUAUCUCCCCCUCUGGCUCAGUCAUCGCCUGCCCACCCUUCACUUCUUAAAGGUGCGCAAGAGAGGAGGGCCGACUGGAGGGUGUCGCCGGAAGGUUUCAGCCUGCCCUUCACAAUUCCCCUUGUGCACAGCCCAGUUUCCAUCUCUCAGGGCCCACCCAGGAAAAUGGAUUUCAAGUGGGGGUUUUCAUCCAGAGAUUUGUUUAACACAAAACAAGAAAAGCUGAGAGGCAAAACAGGGGAGUGAGGGGCAACCCAGAGGUGGGGAACAACAACAGCAAGCCGCCCCCAUCCUGAGACUGGCUGGGCACCAGGGGAGGACGCGUCACCAGAGCCUGGGGCCAAGGCCACUGGGGGACCUGCCACACUGUGGACCUGUCUGGUGGGGGCUGGAGCCUCGAGAAGCCAUGAUUCUUGUCAGAAACAUUUCCCCAGGCAGAGAGAGGGGGCCCCAGCCUCUCCCCUCCUCUUGGCCUCCAGAGUCCUGCAGGUGCCUCACAGUAGUGAAACCCAGUUGGAAGCAGCUGCCCUGGGAGCCUGGGACAGGCGACCCACCGGGUCAGUCCCCUGCCACUCAGAGCAGAGCAGGGGGCUGAGGGCAAGCAGGUGGGGCUGUGCGUGGCCUCAGUGCACUCGGUGUCAUGUCUGAGCCUGGUGUUUAUGCCCCACUGCUGUCCUAAGUCCCUGGCGAGGGGAGGUGGAGGAGCUGCCCCGUGGGUGUUUGGAGAUUCUGUUUUACUCUGCCUAGAGAGGAAACGGCUUUGGGGAGGGAGGGGGAAGCCUUUAUUCUUUACUGUUGUCCCUGUUUUCCUUUGGGGGAAUUUACUCAGUUAGCAGCCCCUCCUCACCAUUCCCCCCAGGAAGGCCAUGUCCCAGUUUUCUGUCCACCCCUCCUGUUCCUCUGCACUAUGUCUCUGAUUUUCCCUGCCAGGGAAGCUAACCCAGAGCACGCACCUGUGCUCAUGAGUGUUUCCGCAGGAUAAUUCGUUCUGAGCAUGAUACCACAGUGUGGAUUGUCUGUCUGUAAGGAGAUGCCAUCUACUAACCAAUUUGUAUUGUGUUUCCAAUAAAUUCCUGGAAAUUUU